AGCAGAGCCUGGGCAGGUGACGGGCGGGCGCGGGCGUCGCAGCUGAGGGAGUAAGGAGGCUCCCAGGAACCGGAGCUGGAAACCCGGCCGAGGUCCAGCCAGAGCCCAAGUAAGAGGGAGCUGGCCUGGGCUCUGCUCUCCUGGGCUGGGGCGCAGGCAGGGCUCAGGCAGGCUGGGGCUGGACGCAAAGGACCUCAAACUUGGAGGGCCUAGCUGGGGAGAGGGUGCAGCCACCCAGUCGUUUCCCUGUGUCUUGGAGUCUGGUGUGGGCACGAAGGGCAGAAGCACAGCCUGGUGGGGGGUUCCUCAACACCGACCCCAUGUUCCUGGCAGGAGCCAGAGUGACCCCUCGACCUGUCAGCCAUGGGGGAGAUGGAGCAACUGCGUCAGGAAGCGGAGCAGCUCAAGAAGCAGAUUGCAGAUGCCAGGAAAGCCUGUGCUGACGUUACUCUGGCAGAGCUGGUGUCUGGCCUAGAGGUGGUGGGACGAGUCCAGAUGCGGACGCGGCGGACGUUAAGGGGACACCUGGCCAAGAUUUACGCCAUGCACUGGGCCACUGAUUCUAAGCUGCUGGUAAGUGCCUCGCAAGAUGGGAAGCUGAUCGUGUGGGACAGCUACACCACCAACAAGGUGCACGCCAUCCCACUGCGCUCCUCCUGGGUCAUGACCUGUGCCUAUGCCCCAUCAGGGAACUUUGUGGCAUGUGGGGGGCUGGACAACAUGUGUUCCAUCUACAACCUCAAAUCCCGUGAGGGCAAUGUCAAGGUCAGCCGGGAGCUUUCUGCUCACACAGGUUAUCUCUCCUGCUGCCGCUUCCUGGAUGACAACAAUAUUGUGACCAGCUCGGGGGACACCACGUGUGCCUUGUGGGACAUUGAGACUGGGCAGCAGAAGACUGUAUUUGUGGGACACACGGGUGACUGCAUGAGCCUGGCUGUGUCUCCUGACUUCAAUCUCUUCAUUUCGGGGGCCUGUGAUGCCAGUGCCAAGCUCUGGGAUGUGCGAGAGGGGACCUGCCGUCAGACUUUCACUGGCCACGAGUCGGACAUCAACGCCAUCUGUUUCUUCCCCAAUGGAGAGGCCAUCUGCACGGGCUCGGAUGACGCUUCCUGCCGCUUGUUUGACCUGCGGGCAGACCAGGAGCUGAUCUGCUUCUCCCACGAGAGCAUCAUCUGCGGCAUCACGUCCGUGGCCUUCUCCCUCAGUGGCCGCCUACUAUUCGCUGGCUACGACGACUUCAACUGCAAUGUCUGGGACUCCAUGAAGUCUGAGCGUGUGGGUAAGGGCCAGCCCUGGCUGCUGCUUCCUCAGCUGGAAGGACCCUCCCCAGCCCUCCCUCCCCAUUCUGUACCCCCCAUCAGCUCCCAUUUCGGACUCUCUUACUGCUGUCCCUUGUCACUGGGUGACUCCACCCCUGGAAUCCAGUACCCCUUGGUUCCCAACUAGGACUGUUUUCCCUCAGUGUUGCUCUAAGCAGCCUCUCUCCACUGCCCAAUGCCAUGACUGCUCCCUGCCCUAGGAGAUCUGUGGACCAUGACUGUCCAGUCAGUUCUGGGUUCCUGGCAUUUCAGGGGCACCCACUGAGAGGCAAGACAGCCUCAGGGAAACAUGGAAUCAAGGCAGAAUCAAGGAGAUCUGGAGUGGCCCGAGGGCCCUGACUGCAGCCUAGGGCUCAUCUAAGACUAGCCUGAAGUUGGUCAGAUAGGAUGGCUUCUUCUCUAUCAAGAGGCCAGGUGCUGAUGAAAAUAACACUGGCCAGGGGCAGAAUCCAAAUCCUAAUUCUGUUGCUCACUUUCUGAGUGUCCUUGCACAAGUCACUCCUCCAUGGGCCUCAGUUUCUUCAUCUGGAAGCAAAGAAAUAGGAUGAACGGUUGCCUUCUCUUUUCCAGCACCUGUCAAGGUGCCCUCGGGUUUUUUCAUAGUACACAGAUGCUUCCAGCCUUUCUCUGUCUGAUCCCAGCCCUCCCCCAACCAAAGCUCUUGACAGAGAACCCCCUGCCCUACAGCUAAUCCUCUUUCAGUCUCUUAGCCUUCUUCAGGGGUUGAGCCCAGUCUACCGAGUCUAGGAUCCCUGCAUGCAUGUGCUCAAGCACACAUGCACACACACACGUACACACACCCACACAUGCAUACACAUGCACACAUAUCCCCCCACACACCCACAUACACACACACACCCACACACCCACACAUACACUUACACGCAUGCACACACUGCUUUCCAAAUCAGCUUGGAGAGACAGGCUGACUCCUUUCCCUCUUCCUCAGGCAUCCUCUCUGGCCACGAUAACAGGGUGAGCUGCCUGGGAGUCACAGCUGACGGGAUGGCUGUGGCCACAGGUUCCUGGGACAGCUUCCUCAAAAUCUGGAACUGAGGAGGCUGGAGAAAGGGAAGUGGAAGGCAGUGAACACACUCAGCAGCCCCCUGCCCGACCCCAUCUCAUUCAGGUGUUCUCUUCUAUAUUCCGGGUGCCAUUCCCACUAAGCUUUCUCCUUUGAGGGCAGUGGGGAGCAUGGGACUGUGCCUUUGGGAGGCAGCAUCAGGGACACAGGGGCAAAGAACUGCCCCAUCUCCUCCCAUGGCCUUCCCUCCCCACAGUCCUCACAGCCUCUCCCUUAAUGAGCAAGGACAACCUGCCCCUCCCCAGCCCUUUGCAGGCCCAGCAGACUUGAGUCUGAGGCCCCAGGCCCUAGGAUUCCUCCCCCAGAGCCACUACCUUUGUCCAGGCCUGGGUGGUAUAGGGCGUUUGGCCCUGUGACUAUGGCUCUGGCACCACUAGGGUCCUGGCCCUCUUCUUAUUCAUGCUUUCUCCUUUUUCUACCUUUUUUUCUCUCCUAAGACACCUGCAAUAAAGUGUAGCACCCUGGUA